AGGGUUUGCCAGGCGAAGGCGGAGCGCUAACGUCUAACGCUAACGGCGGUCGUGCCCCGCCGCUGCUGUCACCCCCGGCCGCUGCUGCCCUCCCCGCCGAGGUUCUACUGCUCUCCUUCUUAAGAAGGGUGGGAGGCACUCGGUCUCUCCCCACACCUCUCGCCUGAGGCCAGGCGCCAGGUGUCGCCUGAAGCCAGACAGCCGGUUUGGGAGCGAGCCUGAGUUCCAGGCACUGGGCUAGGCACUGGGAUGGUGUGGUGAGCAAAAACUGACCAGUCCUGCCGUGGAGUUUGCUGGGGGAGACACAUGUUACUCAAAGAAUCACACUAAGGAUAGCAAUUUAUCUCAAAGCUUCAAGUUCCUGCCAUCUACAUGUGCCCAGGUCAACCAAUCAAUGGCUCAGACAGAUAAGCCAACAUGCAUCCCGCCGGAGCUGCCGAAAAUGCUGAAGGAGUUUGCCAAAGCCGCCAUUCGGGCGCAGCCGCAGGACCUCAUCCAGUGGGGGGCCGAUUAUUUUGAGGCCCUGUCCCGUGGAGAGACGCCUCCGGUGAGAGAGCGGUCUGAGCGAGUCGCUUUGUGUAACUGGGCAGAGCUAACACCUGAGCUGUUAAAGAUCCUGCAUUCUCAGGUUGCUGGCAGACUGAUCAUCCGUGCAGAGGAGCUGGCCCAGAUGUGGAAAGUGGUGAAUCUCCCAACAGAUCUGUUUAAUAGUGUGAUGAAUGUGGGUCGCUUCACGGAGGAGAUCGAGUGGCUGAAGUUUUUAGCCCUUGCUUGCAGCGCUCUGGGAGUUACUAUUACCAAAACUCUCAAGAUAGUGUGUGAGGUCUUAUCAUGUGACCACAAUGGUGGGUUGCCCCGAAUCCCAUUCAGCACCUUCCAGUUUCUCUACACGUAUAUUGCCGAAGUGGAUGGGGAGAUCUGUGCAUCACAUGUCAGCAGGAUGCUAAACUACAUUGAACAGGAAGUAAUUGGUCCUGAUGGUUUAAUCACGGUGAAUGACUUUACCCAAAACCCCAGGGUUUGGCUGGAGUAACAGCACAAUUUUGGCAAUUUUAAAGGAAGAUACAGAGGUGAUUGUACUUCAGAAUGAUAAACCCAUAUACCACCUAAAAUCAAUUUUCUUGUACAACUGGUACACACUAAUAAACAAACAUGUGAGAUCAGAAA